GUUUCUGCGUCUGCCGUGGACAGCGAAGCUGCUGCGGUUCCUGAGCCGGAGGAGUGCCUGUGAAGAAAACGGGGUAUUGCCCUGAGGCUUAUAUUCUGCCUCAGUUGUCUUUUCUUGAAAUAUUAUAAAUCAGAAUGUCUGCACAGUCAGUGGAAGAAGAUUCAAUACUUAUCAUCCCAACUCCAGAUGAAGAGGAAAAAAUUCUGAGAGUGAAGUUGGAGGAGGAUCCUGAUGGCGAAGAGGGAUCAAGUAUCCCCUGGAACCAUCUCCCAGACCCAGAGAUUUUCCGACAGCGAUUCAGGCAGUUUGGAUACCAGGAUUCACCUGGGCCCCGUGAGGCUGUGAGCCAGCUCCGAGAACUUUGCCGUCUGUGGCUCAGGCCAGAGACGCACACAAAAGAACAAAUCUUGGAGCUGGUAGUGCUGGAGCAGUUUGUUGCCAUCCUACCCAAAGAGCUACAGACUUGGGUUCGAGAUCAUCAUCCAGAGAAUGGAGAGGAGGCAGUGACAGUGCUGGAGGAUUUGGAGAGUGAACUUGAUGACCCUGGACAACCGGUUUCUCUCCGUCGACGAAAACGGGAAGUACUAGUAGAAGACAUGGUAUCUCAAGAAGAAGCUCAGGGAUUACCAAGUUCUGAGCUUGAUGCUGUGGAGAACCAGCUCAAGUGGGCAUCCUGGGAGCUCCAUUCCCUAAGGCACUGUGUAAUCAUUCCUUGAAGUAGUUGGAGAUGGUGCUGGUAUGCCACUGAAUGAGGUCUGAGCAGGUUUUCUUCACAUCUGAGGGGACAGUGCCAGCCAGUCAACUUUUGGGGUGGGGCUGAAGUCUGCUGAAAAUCUGCAGUUUUACAUGUUUCAUGGGACAUUCUUCUGUGCAAUAAAGUUUGAGAAGUAUCAUUCUUGAUAUAUGGGGCUGAUAUUUUCAACUUCUCAUCAUCUGAAUUUUAGAGUGACUUUUCACCUGCGUUCCUUAUUUCAGCUGUCUAGUCUCUUCCACACUUGGGAAUUUCUGUUUCCUGUGUGCCGUUUGUCUCCACUUAAUCUUCACGCUCCUCUGUUUUUCAAGUCUCCAAGCCUCACUAUCCUCCUCUAACCUUUCAGUCUCUCUCUCUUAGCCUUAUCUCCUGACUUGAUCUUUUUGUUAAUUAUUUACUGUUUUCCUCUUCGCUGAAGGCAGUUGCUAACCCUAUAUGAACUGGAUCUUUACUCCUUAAGGCAUGAAGUUUUAGAAAAGUCUUAAAUGACACUUGCUGUUAUCUCUGCCUGCGUGUGAGUGAUGCUAACCCAUGUUGGUAAUUCAGGCUUUUCUUUCAUUGGACACGUUUCACUGAGGCUUAGAAAUAACGAUUUUUCUAAGUACCAUGACAAAUACCACAUGGGAGAAGCUGCUUUUAUUGGAAAACUUUCAUUUAUUAGGGGCAUACUGAAUUUUUAUGUCAUGUCUUUGGUUAACACAGGAGGCCCCCAGCUUAUCUUCAGCCCCUUCUUGUCAAGACUCCUGUGUUCUGCUUUUAGGCUAACAUUGGCUGUGACCUGACUUGGCUUGUUCAUUUCAGAAAUAGCCACUUUCUGACAUGUUUUUCUAAUUUACAUCUUUGUAUUUUGAUGUAAUUUCUCCCUUUCUCAAAGUAAAAGAACAUUAUAAUGAUUUCCUAGUGGCCAAUUUUAUUUUAUUUUUAUUCUUACAAAGUUUCAUCCAUACCUAGCCACAUCAUUUUGACUAUCUCCCUAACCAUCUUAGAAUCUACCAUCUUUCUGACCUUUGUUUUCUGACUACCAUUUGUAAACCACUUGCCUAUGUUUUAUUCAGAUAUCCCUUAUAUCAUGAUGUUAUACUGUUAUUCAGAGUAAUUUCAUUUUUUCUUUUUUGAGAAUAGGCCUUAACACCAGUGUCAGAGUGGUUUAUAGAUGUGUGCUAGCUAUUUUAGUUCAUUAAAAAAAAAAUUUUUUUUAGGUUUCUUUUCCCUUAAUAGAUAAUGAAUGAUAUUUACAUUUUCUGUUUAUUUCAGAUGAUGAUGGUAGGACUGAAAAUGGAGCACUAGCUCCAAAGCAGGAGCUUCCUUCAGCAUUAGAAUCCCAUGAAGUUCCUGGCACUCUCAAUAUGGGUGUUCCUCAAAUUUUUAAAUAUGGAGAAACCUGUUUCCCCAAGGGCAGGUUUGAAAGAAAGAGAAAUCCCUCUCGAAAGAAACAACAUAUAUGUGAUGAAUGUGGAAAACACUUCAGUCAGGGCUCAGCCCUUAUUCUUCAUCAAAGAAUUCACAGUGGGGAGAAACCUUAUGGAUGUGUUGAGUGUGGGAAAGCAUUCAGCCGAAGUUCCAUUCUUGUGCAACACCAGAGAGUCCACACUGGAGAAAAACCUUACAAAUGUCUUGAAUGUGGGAAAGCCUUUAGCCAGAAUUCGGGGCUUAUUAAUCAUCAGAGAAUCCAUACUGGGGAGAAACCUUAUGAAUGCGUUCAGUGUGGGAAAUCGUAUAGUCAAAGCUCAAAUCUUUUUAGACAUCAGAGAAGACACAAUGCAGAAAAACUUCUGAAUGUUGUGAAAGUUUAAGAAAUUGAAAAAAAAAAAAGAAUCAGCACUCAGGUCUUUUUCUUCAGAAAUGAAGACAAAAUUUAAAAUAUGAAAUGAUGCAGAAUAGUUUUUUCCCUAUUGACUGUCAGAAAAUCCACUGGGAAAUGUAAAAAUCUUCACUCACCAUUAUGAUAUUUAUCUUGAAAGAAAUGGUGUCAUACCUGCCUAGAAACUGAAAUUUUAAACUUAAUUCAGGUCUUAAUGCCUAAAUUUUCCAUGUGAUGUUUAUAGUCUGUAUUACUUCUCCAAAUAAUGAACUACCUGAUUCAUUGUCCCUUUCUUGAAAGUUUCUUUUUUAAGACAAAUACAUUAUUUCUGCAUUGAUCAUUGAAAUGUUCUUUAUAUGGAUACAUUCCCUUAUAUAUUAAAAGGCAACAGGAAUUACAAAGUCUGAAAACCAUUUUAAACCAUCUUUUAAAAAUUUACCCUUAUUUCCUUUUACCUAAUUUGAAUAUGCAUUUGAGAAAAUAAGAGGAUAAAGGAUGGCUAAGAGCCUCAAAAUGAACCAUAAGAUCUCAGAUAAGAAGUGAUGGUGAUAAAACAUCAAAAAGUGAAUGGAACACCUUGAUUGGGGAAGAUAUGCAAAUACUUUGAUCUAAGAAUUGAAAUGUAUCAAGAAUUUAUAUUUUGCCUGCAGGAAAAUUCAAAAGCUACUCAUCCUCUCUAUAAUUUGGAGUCAUCUUACUAAUGAAAAUAAUGUUUUCCCAUAUAUUAUUAAAAAGCAUACAGUCUAAAUAAUAAACAGUUGUAAAAUAAUGAAGGUAGAAAUUAUAACACUAGGGAAAAAUUUGUAGCGGAUGGCAGUGUUGAAGGCAAAUGUAAACAUAAGGGUAAUGGUCUGUCAUGGCUUUUAGAAAAAGAUGAUAGAGUUCAUCAUUAUUUUGCCUUCAUCUUUGUUAAGGACAGAAAAUUCCCUGACAGGUGGGCAAGUAUCAGGUUACCUAUUUUUUAUUCCUUUGGUACAAAAGGGUUGAACGUCAGGCUAAAAAAGCAGCCAUGCAUUUAUUAUUAAACAUUUUCUACCGACAAGGCACUGUGCUAGGUACUGUAAUCCUACCAUAAGUAGGUAGGUAUUUCUUCCACUGUAAAUCAUAGGGGUUUGCUGUUUUAUGUGAGUUAGCCUCUUCCCCUUGUCUGAGCAUUCCUCAGGGGAGGUCACCUGUGAGGUUCCCAGAACUGUAGUUUUUUUUACCAGGGUGUUGUAUUUGGAGGGGGAGGAGGACUCGGCUCAAAAGAGCUAGCUGGCUCUCCAGUGUUCAGAGGUGAGUCCACGAUACUCUUACCACAAUUUGGAAGUUUGUGAAUCUUUUUAAAGAACUAAUCAAUCUCUAAUAGCAUUGAGGUUGUACCUACAUAUUAAGUUGAAUGGACUGUUCUAUUUAAAAAAUAAACAACUAGACAAUUAACUAGUUUAUUAACCUAUCACAAUUGAAUUUUUUUUUAAUUUUCAGUCUUAACACAUUUUUUAAAAUGUAUUAAAGUAAUACAUUGUAGUAGUAGGAUUAUAUACUCCUUGGCUGAGAAUUCCAAGUACUGUGGUUCUACUGUUUAGUGGAAAACUCUGGAAGUUAAAAUAUAGAAUAUGAGAGGAGGCUUUUUUAUAAUGGGCAUCAUUGUGUGGAAAAUGACCCAUGUGAAUACAAAUAUUUCCUAGUUCAGAGAUUUUGGUUAUAUCUGGUGCUUGGAUCAAGUUUAAAAAUGGAAGGUGAGAUUUUGCAUGAGCCUAUUAAAAAGCAUAGUAAUAAAUGCAAGGCCAGCUGGUGGAAAAGUGAGGCAGAAUGGAGCUUGUUUAUAGGUUUUCUGAUAACAAUUAUAAAAAAUGUGCUUUAUAGAUUAAGAUUUAUUGAAGUAUAAAUAUGUAGUAAUGAUAUAAUGUAUUUUAAGUUAUACAAGAAAAUGUAGGGACUUUUGUUUGGGUCUUUUUCUCUUUGUGGCUGAGGGGAAACAAGUCAGUGUCCAAUAAAGCUGUAAACUCCUCUGCUCUAAGAUAAAUGAUGUGAUUUAUUUAUUUAUAACUGGCUUCUUUCCAAGUAGGUUUUCAGGUGGCAUAUUUGGAAGACGGCUGGAAUGACAGAAUUCUUGUAUCAGAGUAGGUAAGAAGGGAGCAACCUCUCAAUGGCUAUUAUGUCAUGCUUUUUAAGAUCGUAUGCGGUUCCUAUAUACAAGGAAGCUUCCCUGUGGUAGAUUUGUCAUAAAUGCCAAAGAUAUUUGGUAAUGUGAGUGUAGAAAAAGUAGUAUGAGGGUUGGCAAAUACUGUUUUUGUCUUGGCAGCUCUAAUAUCUGCAUUGUUCAGAAAGGAUUCUGAGGCUAAGGCAAAGCUCUGUGGGAAAAAGGGACUGGACCAAAAAAAACUGGAUGGUGGCACACAAGAAGAGGAAAUGAUGAGAUGUGUACUUUCUAUCUCUGGUUAGGCUUAGUCCCCACUAGACAAAUUGAUUUUAAAUACUAUGUAGUGAUUUUUAAAUUCCAUCCACACAUUCAUUACCCACACAGAUAAUCAUAGAAAUUUGGGGGAGUGCCUAGCUUCUGAUGAAGUGGUGAUAUGGCAGUGCCAAGCAGUGGCAUCGCCAGAGUAUCUGUUUGGUUAGCAAAUGAGCAGUCAUUUUAGGUCAUGCAGAUUGCUGAUAUCUGCCCAGUAGCCACUGAGCAUUUGCUGGUUUUUUCUUCUGGCUUUCUUGGAGGUUAAGCUCUCUGUAGUCAUACCCAGUUGGUACUUGAUCUUUAGCAAUAUGUCUCAUAUUCAUGUAAAUUGAAGGGAGGGUUACAUGUACUGAAAUAAUCUGCAUGCUAGGCAUUGGCUUAGACACCGUACCUAUCUCACUUAGAUUUGUGGACUAGGAAAGCAAGAUUCAGAGAUCAUGUGACUUGCAUGUGGCCUAGAGAUAAAAUUCAAAUCUGGUUCUGUAGACUCCAGGGACAUAUUCACCAUGCCAUGGGUGGUGGCUAUUAAACCUUGAUAAAUUUGUGUUUAUGGUUAACAAAUGUGAAAGCUAUUAAACAUUGCUGGUUUGAAUUUUUUACAGUGCAGAAAUGUAAAAUGAAAAAGGAUAUUUCCUUUCACAGUGUUACCGAGAAGUCAUGAUAAUUUCGUUUGUUCUUCCAGAUUUAGGCAUAUACUUAUUUAAUCAAUAAUGUGUUAACAGCUGACACCUGUGGUUGCUGUGACAGGCACUAUUUGAAGUGCUUUAUCAUGGAUUAACUCUUAAUCCUCAGCUACCGUAUAAAGUAGGACAUAACCCCAUUUCACAUGCACUACACUGAGACUUGCCUCCUCUCCCCCCACAUUGAAGAUGUUCUUUUUUCAUAACUAUAUACUAUUCCAUUGCAUGAAUAUUCUGUAAUUUAUUUAAUCCCCUAUGGAUUGAUAAUUAGGUUCAUUAUAGAUAGAAGUGUAAUUAACAUUCCUGUACAUGUAUUUUGCUACUUGUGUGGGUAUUUCUGUAGGAUGAAUAACUAGAAAUUUAUUGGAUCAGGUUUCACAUUUGCAGUUUUGAAAACUACUACCAAAAAGAUUUCACCAAUUUACAACUCCAUCAUUAGUAAGAAUGCCUGUUUGCCUAUAGUCUGCCAACCCUGAAUCCUUAAAAAUUUUUGCCAAUCUGGUAGGCAAAAUUUCUUUCUUUUCUUUGAAUAUUAAUGAGGAGGAACAUCUUUUCAUGUUUCUUGGCCAUUUGCAUUUCCUAUUAUGAAUUGCUUUUGCCCAUUUUCCUUUUUUUAAUUAUGAAAGUCUAAUGACUACCUUCUCAUUGUAUAAAAAACACAGUUCUUUGAAUAGAGAGACCCUUUUCUCCAAUGCUACCAAUCACAUUCCACUUACCACAGUUUAACAUACAUCCUCUAGUCACCUUUCCGUACGAAUAUACAUACACAUAAAAACACUUUUUACAUAAAUAGGAUCUCAUAUUCUGUAGCUUUUUAAAAUUUUGGUCUCAAAAAAAGAUAACAGGUCUUUAAAUUUCUUUAAUGGUUGAAUAUGAUUAAAUACUAUGAAAAUGCCAUUAUUUAUUCCCUUAAUUUUUUUCCUCUCGCUAUUACAUUGCCAAAGUAAACAUCCUAUUCAGAUGUCUUUGUGCAUGUGUGUGAAUAUUUCUUUAGUCUGGAGUCCAGUAAGGUGGAUUUUUGGAUCAAAGGGUUUGUUCUCUGUCCACCUUCAGUCUUCCCAAAGGCCUUCAUAACUGUAUUUUCACCAAGUGUAUGGAGAAUGUUCAUUUCCCCAUAUAACCAUACCUACACUUGAUAGUUUUUAUCUGUUGGGCGAAAAAGAACCUUUUCUUAUUUUGCAUUUCCCUGAUUAUAAAAAAAAAUGGUGAGAUUGGGGUUAUUUUCAUGUUUAUUGGCCAUUUAUAGUUUACUGUGGAUUGUUUGUAUCCCUUACCUGCUUUCUAUUGGGUUAUGUGUGGAUAUAUUGUUUUUAUUUGUUCAGCAUCUCCUUCCCCAUCUUCUGGUAACACAACCUUUAUUUAUUUGUGGGGAACCUAUUCCCUGUGGCUUAGGUGAGCAUGUGACCAGGCCUGGCCUCCUGAGUCCCACAGCUUCCUAGCCACAGUGAUAAAAGAAUGGGUAUAUAACUUAAGCCAGGCUAAGGAAAGCCCUUAACAGAACUUCUGCUGGAACUACUGGAAAGAAGGCUUUAUGGAGAUCCCAGGAACCAAGGACCAUGUAAGCCUGAAUUUGUGCCAUGUGGAGAGAGUCUGUCUGAGGAGAAACUCGGAUGCUAGCAGAAAUGGAAAGAGAACUAAGUUCUGAUGUCAUUUUUCUGGAGGCCCUAGAUCCAGCUGUGCCUAAAGCCUGCCCUACCUCCGGACUUUAAAGUUUUGUGAGCCAAUAAAGUCCCUUUCUUGUUUAAGAUAAUUGAAUUGAGUUUCUGUUCUGAUUAAUAUAGGUUAUUUGUAUUUUCUUAUUGAUUUGUAGAAAACCUUUGUAAUUUUAAAUUCUAGACUUUAUGCACUAUAUAAGUUAAUAAAAUUAGCAUGGCCUUCCAUGA